GUCUUGCCGCGGCUCCCGGGAUGCGCGGAGGCGGUGGCGAUGGCGAUGAUGCCUCUAGUCCUGCAUCAUCCAGAGCGGCAGGCGGAGCUGGGGUCCGGACUGCGAGAUGGAGGAGGGGCGGCGCUGCGGCCACCCGGCAGACUGGUCAAACAAAUGGAUUUUACAGAGGCUUACGCGGACACGUGCUCUACAGUUGGACUUGCUGCCAGGGAAGGCAAUGUUAAAGUCUUAAGGAAACUGCUCAAAAAGGGCCGAAGUGUCGAUGUUGCUGAUAACAGGGGAUGGAUGCCAAUUCAUGAAGCAGCUUAUCACAACUCUGUAGAAUGUUUGCAAAUGUUAAUUAAUGCAGAUUCAUCUGAAAACUACAUUAAGAUGAAGACCUUUGAAGGUUUCUGUGCUUUGCAUCUCGCUGCAAGUCAAGGACAUUGGAAAAUCGUACAGAUUCUUUUAGAAGCUGGGGCAGAUCCUAAUGCAACUACUUUAGAAGAAACGACACCAUUGUUUUUAGCUGUUGAAAAUGGACAGAUAGAUGUGUUAAGGCUGUUGCUUCAACACGGAGCAAAUGUUAAUGGAUCCCAUUCUAUGUGUGGAUGGAACUCCUUGCACCAGGCUUCUUUUCAGGAAAAUGCUGAGAUCAUAAAAUUGCUUCUUAGAAAAGGAGCAAACAAGGAAUGCCAGGAUGACUUUGGAAUCACACCUUUAUUUGUGGCUGCUCAGUAUGGCAAGCUAGAAAGCUUGAGCAUACUUAUUUCAUCGGGUGCAAAUGUCAAUUGUCAAGCCUUGGACAAAGCUACACCCUUGUUCAUUGCUGCUCAAGAGGGACACACAAAAUGUGUGGAGCUUUUGCUCUCCAGUGGGGCAGAUCCUGAUCUUUACUGUAAUGAGGACAGUUGGCAGUUACCUAUUCAUGCAGCUGCACAAAUGGGCCAUACAAAAAUCUUGGACUUGUUAAUACCACUUACUAACCGGGCCUGUGACACUGGGCUAAACAAAGUAAGCCCUGUUUACUCAGCAGUGUUUGGGGGACAUGAAGAUUGCCUAGAAAUAUUACUCCGGAAUGGCUACAGCCCAGACGCCCAGGCGUGCCUUGUUUUUGGAUUCAGUUCUCCUGUGUGCAUGGCUUUCCAAAAGGACUGUGAGUUCUUUGGAAUUGUGAACAUUCUUUUGAAAUAUGGAGCCCAGAUAAAUGAACUUCAUUUGGCAUACUGCCUGAAGUACGAGAAGUUUUCGAUAUUUCGCUACUUUUUGAGGAAAGGUUGCUCAUUGGGACCAUGGAACCAUAUAUAUGAAUUUGUAAAUCAUGCAAUUAAAGCACAAGCAAAAUAUAAGGAGUGGUUGCCACAUCUUCUGGUUGCUGGAUUUGACCCACUGAUUCUACUGUGCAAUUCUUGGAUUGACUCAGUCAGCAUUGACACCCUUAUCUUCACUUUGGAGUUUACUAAUUGGAAGACACUUGCACCAGCUGUUGAAAGGAUGCUCUCUGCUCGUGCCUCAAACGCUUGGAUUCUACAGCAACAUAUUGCCACUGUUCCAUCCCUGACCCAUCUUUGUCGUUUGGAAAUUCGGUCCAGUCUAAAAUCAGAACGUCUACGGUCUGACAGUUAUAUUAGUCAGCUGCCACUUCCCAGAAGCCUACAUAAUUAUUUGCUCUAUGAAGACGUUCUGAGGAUGUAUGAAGUUCCAGAACUGGCAGCUAUUCAAGAUGGAUAAAUCAGUGAAACUACUUAACACAGCUAAUUUUUUUCUCUGAAAAAUCAUCGAGACAAAAGAGCCACAGAGUACAAGUUUUUAUGAUUUUAUAGUCAAAAGAUGAUUAUUGAUUGUGAGAUAGGUUAGGUUUUGGGGGGCCAGUAGUUCAGUGAGAAUGUUUAUGUUUACAACUAGCCUUCCCAGUAAAAAAAAAAAAAAAAAAAAAAAAAA